ACUCUUAAGGUUCCGAUCACAGACUGCGGAGUGGGUCAGGGGCUGCGAGGGCUGCCCCAAGUCCUACCGGGUUUGCACGGGCGCGCCCGGCUCCGCCCGCAAGUGCGCCUUCCUGACUUACUGCUGGGUGCGCGGGGCUGGGGGUGCGAGUACCACCCCUGAAGUCUCUUCCUGGGCGACCUCCGGGGCCUCAUUCUAGGCCUCCUUAAAGAGAAGGAUCUAAAUUAGGAAAAGGAAGUGCCCUUAUCCACGACCAAGCUCUUCCACCUGCGGAGCUCGCUUAGUCUGCACCUCAACCGUGCGGAAAGUGACUGCCCUGUUUACUGAGGAAAAACUGGGGCUCAGAAAGAUACCAUGGAGUAGUUUGAAACAGGAACAAAAUCUUCUGAAAGCUCGGAGCAGAAGCCUUUUUGGUCAACAUGGAGGAAAAAAGACGGCGAGCCCGAGUUCAGGGAGCCUGGGCUGCCCCUGUUAAAAGCCAGGCCAUUGCUCAGCCAGCUACCACUGCUAAGAGCCAUCUCCACCAGAAGCCUGGCCAGACCUGGAAGAACAAAGAGCAUCAUCUCUCUGACAGAGAGUUUGUGUUCAAAGAACCUCAGCAGGUAGUACGUAGAGCUCCUGAGCCACGAGUGAUUGACAGAGAGGGUGUGUAUGAAAUCAGCCUGUCACCCACAGGUGUAUCUAGGGUCUGUUUGUAUCCUGGCUUUGUUGACGUGAAAGAAGCUGACUGGAUAUUGGAACAGCUUUGUCAAGAUGUUCCCUGGAAACAGAGGACUGGCAUCAGAGAGGAUAUAACUUAUCAGCAACCAAGACUUACAGCAUGGUAUGGAGAACUUCCUUACACUUAUUCAAGAAUCACUAUGGAACCAAAUCCUCACUGGCACCCUGUGCUGCGCACACUAAAGAACCGCAUUGAAGAGAACACUGGCCACACCUUCAACUCCUUACUCUGCAAUCUUUAUCGCAAUGAGAAGGACAGCGUGGACUGGCACAGUGAUGAUGAACCCUCACUAGGGAGGUGCCCCAUUAUUGCUUCACUAAGUUUUGGUGCCACACGCACAUUUGAGAUGAGAAAGAAGCCACCACCAGAAGAGAAUGGAGACUACACAUAUGUGGAAAGAGUGAAGAUACCCUUGGAUCAUGGGACCUUGUUAAUCAUGGAAGGAGCGACACAAGCUGACUGGCAGCAUCGAGUGCCCAAAGAAUACCACUCUAGAGAACCGAGAGUGAACCUGACCUUUCGGACAGUCUAUCCAGACCCUCGAGGGGCACCCUGGUGACGUCAGAGCUUUGAGAGAGAAGCUUCACUGAAACGGAGCAAACCUUCCACUGAGAAGCCACUUCAAGAGGCUGGUGCUGCUAGAUCUCAUGAUGUGGCUGUUGGGAAGAUGGUGGGGUUUGUUUGCCAGCUUGGAGUCCUAUUAAAUGAAAGCCAGCAACUCAUGUUGGUAAUAGGUCUACUGUGGGAACAGUUAUCCCUAACCACAGCUCAAAAUCGCUAUCAUCUUUAGGCAAAUUAAAAUCUAUGUGGCAGUGCUCAUGGA